GAGGCAAACUGAAGGUCAUCGUCCCUUCCCAGGUGGUAGAAAGUGGGGCCCUGGGAUAAGCAGGGUACUGGCUGGAUUCCCGGAUCUGUAGCCCUCCUUUGCUGCCGUUUCCACGGCCCUUUGGCAUCUUCCUCUCUCCUGCAUGAGGGACUGCAGGGCGACGGGCAUCCGCAGCUCCCUCUAGUCGGCAGGAAGUAGGUUCCUGGCUGAGAGAGACUUGGCACCACGGCACAUCGCUGCUGAUCAGCCUUUAUAGAGCCAUAUGCAUCACUUUAGAGAAAGAAAGGAGAAAAAUUAGAGUGGCGGGAAAGCAAUUUCCGUUGCAAUUUAAAAGGCGGCUAUUAAAAUUUUAUAAGAGCUUUAUUGCAGGGGUUUUCUGAUCAUCCCAGGAAUUUUUAAAAUGGGAAGUCUAGUGAUAAAGGAAAAUGUUCUGGGUGCGUCUGGUUCCCUCCUGCCCUGCCAAGCAUCUUGAAAACCACCAUUGUGAGGGCUUCCUAGACCAGCUUAGCAAUAGCAACGGCCCAAGAGGCCAUUUCUGAGUGUUUUAAAAGCGUGUUUUUCUGUAUUUGCUGUUUCUAUGUAUAGUGACUGUUUCUAAUUUUAUUUUGUACUUUGCUAAAUGGCCUGGUAGGGAGCUAUGGGAAUCGUCAAGAACAGCAGUUGCCUCUGCCCUUCUGUGUUAGUUGAGAGUCAUUUGGUUGUAUGAACAAAUAGAAAUUCAGGUCAAAAGGAAGUCUAAAAGGAAGUGGAUGGACACAGGGCCUGGGAGAUUCGGCUUGGAAUGGUUUCAGGCAAGGCUGGAUCCAGGGCCUGGUGAGGUUGUCAGGACAUGUUUCCUUUUACCUCCUGGCUCAGCAUUCUUCUGUGCUGAUUUUAUUCUCAGGUAGGCUCUGAAGCAGCCCCUAGCAGCUCCACUAGUAGAUUCAACCAACUUAGCAGCUCCAAGGGAAAUAAACCAUCUCUUUCCCCCAUAGUCCCAGUAUAUAUCAUGGGGCUGGUGUUUACUGGCUCUGAUCAUCCUGGCUUUGGUGGCAGGGUCACCCCGGGCCAUCUCUGAAGCUGGGAACAGGGAAGGUGGUGCAGUGGCUUUUUGGCCAGACUUGGAUCAUAUGACCAGUCCCACCUCCACCCACAACCCAUGGGUGGGGUGAGUCCCAUAGGACUGAGUGGGAAAGAUGAGGUUCAAGGGGCUGACUGAGGAAGAGAAAUAGAUGCAGGGUGGGUCAAAGCAACCGACGCCUGGAACCCCUUCCCAUACUAACUUCACGAAGCUGAAUCUGCCCCCACACUCCCCAGUUGUUCUUUUCCCUUGGAAGCUGCUCCGCCUUUACCUUCUUUCGGGUCUCGUUGAGGGGUUCUUAAUCUCGGGUCCAUGGACCUUUGAAGGAUGGAAGAUUAGUGGGUCACGAGGUUGGCUGGGAAAAACAUUACAUCUCUAUUUUCGCUACCCUGUAACUGAAAUUAACAUUUUUUUAUGCACAGGGCAAUAAACCACAAUUGGAUUAGCAAUAUCUGUGACUUUGUCACUACUAGAAAUCACGGAUAUUCUCAUAUCACAUUACAGUGUUGCAAAUAUCACAAAAUAUCAUUUAAACACCUACCUGUUUCUAAAUCACUAUAGGUAUUGGACUCACCACUAGAUCUUGUAAUAUAACAGCAUUAAUAGGCCAGAAGUGGUGUUUCACACCUGUAAUCCCAGCACUUUGGGAGGCCAAGGUGGGCGGAUCGCUUGAGGCCAGGAGUUUGAGACCAGCCCAGACAACGUGACGAAACCCCAUCUCUACUAAAAAUACAAAAAUUACCUGGGGUGGUGGUGUGUACCUGUAAACCCAGCUACUCGGGAGGCUGAGGCAGAAUUGCUUGAGUCUGGGAGGCAGAGGUUGCAGUGAGCCAAGAUGGCGCCACUGUACUCCAGCCUGGGCAGUAGAUCAAGACUCCAUCUCAAAAAAAAAGAAAUUAUUCUGAGGAGUCUGCAACUAAUUCACCAGGUUGCCAGUAGGAGUCCCUGGCAUGAGAAAGGUUAAGAACCCCCUUGGGCUUCUCCAGGAACCCCAGGGGAAUGAUCAUUGAAGUUGUCCUGAUUCCUGGACCCUGGGGUGUUAGCUAGCUGCUUGCUAGGCUUCCUUCCUGGGAGAUUCCUGGAGGAGCUGACCGGCCUUUGAGGUUGGCGGGGAUAUUUGGGUAGCAUUUGGACAUUAUGGUAUUGGGGAAGUGGAGCAGGGAGGUGUUGCCAGCCCACUGCCUUCAUUGACCAUUGUGACAGAGUGUGGUCUAGCCAGGUGGUCAGAAACAGACUCUGGGACCAGGUUGCUGGGUUCACAUCCUGGCUGUAUAUAGUACACUUUUUUUUUUUUUUUAAACAGGGUCUUGCUAUGUUGCCCAGGCUGGUCUUGAACUUCUGAGCUCAAAUGAUCCUCCCAUCUUAGCCUCCUGAGUAGCUGGGACUAUAGGCUUAGUGGGACUAUAGACCACUGUGCCUAGCUUAGUAUACUUUUGACUGACUGGGCAACCUCAGCUAGUGGGUCCCUUAUGAAUUCUGUGCCUCAGUUUCCUCAUCUGUAACAUGAAAGUAAUAAUAGUAUCUUCUUCUUGGGUGAUCGGGAGAGUGAAAUGAGUCAGCACUUGUCUGCUAGGACAGAGCCGGCACAUUGGGAGGGAUUGUUAUUAGUGAAUGGCCAUUGCAUAUAGGACAGCUCUAGACCCUCUCAGCUCUCAUCUCCUGACUUAGUGCCCAGCCUCUGCCGGUGCCCAGAAUGUGAUGCUGAACAAUACAGACAGUGCCUUCUCCGCCUGGAGACAUUCAUUCAUCCAUGGAAUAUUCACUUAAAUAUAAACAAGCAUACUAAAUAUUCAAAGGCAUAAAUUAAUAAUAUAAAGUUCCAAACCAGGACAAGUAUGAUUUCUCUGUCAUUCCUCUGCUCACAGUUGUCUGAGGAAAUGUCCUUAGAAUAGCCCUUCAUCUGUCCCCCCUGCCACCGCUUGCCCCUCACUCACCCCGUGCCAGCUCCAUGGGCCUCCUGACUGCUCCUGAGAUGCUCCACAUCUGCUCCUGCCCUCUGGAAGGCUCUUUCCCAGAUGCACAGUCUCUGACAUCAGCUCUCCUGGGACCCUCCAAGAGCACUAGUGUCUAGAAGGCACUAAGGCAUGGCGAGGACAACAUCCUUGCUGCCUCCAGCUGGCGGGCGACCACAGCUACUGCCUGCUCUGCGCUACUGAGCCACUCGGUCUGGAGCCCCCAGGACAGCACCUGCUUCCUGAGGUUGUCCUGGCUCAGCUGUGCACAGCGAUGGUGGAGAACUGGACUCCACAGGCUCACAACCUUCCUGUCAGGUUUCAGGGCCCAGCAUCCUUCAUCCUGGGCCUGGCUGCCCUGAACAAUGGCUGAGGGCUGGGGGACCCCAUAGAGUGACACCACAGCGUACGGGGCCAGCAGCACUCCAGUGCCCGUGGACUAUGACCACCUAUCGGGCCAUCCCCAGCGAUGGUGUGGACCUGGCAGCCAGCUGUGGCGCCAGGGUGGGCGAUGUCCUCCCUGGGCCACACACAGGGGACUACGCUCCCUUGGGAUUCUGGGCCCAGAAUGGCAGCAUGUCCCAGCCUCUUGGCGAGAGCCCGGCCACCGCCACCGCCACCGCCACCGCCACCACCCGCCCCAGCCCCACCACUCCCGCAAUGCCCAAGAUGGGCGUGCGCGCAAGGGUGGCCGACUGGCCGCCCAAGCGGGAGGCCCUGAGAGAGCACAGCAACCCAAGCCCCUCCCAGGACACAGAUGGCACAAAGGCCACCAAGAUGGCCCAUUCCAUGAGGAGCAUACAGAACGGACAGCCCCCCACCAGCACCCCGGCUUCCUCAGGGUCCAAAGCCUUCCACCGACUCUCCAGGAGAAGGUCCAAAGACGUGGAGUUCCAGGACGGGUGGCCCCGGUCCCCCGGCAGGGCCUUCCUCCCCCUUCGGCACCGCAGCAGCAGCGAGAUCACCCUCAGCGAGUGUGACGCGGAGGACGCGGGGGAGCCGCGGGGGGCCCGGCACACGGGGGCGCUGCCCCUCUUCCGCGAGUACGGGAGCACCUCGUCCAUCGACGUGCAGGGCAUGCCCGAGCAGAGCUUCUUCGACAUCCUGAACGAGUUCCGCAGCGAGCAGCCCGACGCCCGAGGGUGCCAGGCCCUCACCGAGCUCCUCCGGGCAGAUCCUGGCCCACACCUCAUGGGGGGCGGCGGCGGAGCCAAGGGGGACUCCCACAACGGGCAGCCCGCCAAGGACAGCCUCCUGCCACUGCAGCCCACGAAGGAGAAGGAGAAGGCCCGGAAGAAACCUGCGCGGGGCCUCGGCGGCGGGGACACGGUGGACUCGUCCAUCUUUCGGAAGCUAAGGAGCAGCAAACCCGAGGGGGAGGCUGGGCGUUCCCCGGGGGAGGCCGACGAGGGCCGGAGCCCCCCGGAAGCCAGCAGGCCGUGGGUGUGUCAGAAGAGCUUCGCCCACUUCGACGUGCAGAGCAUGCUGUUCGACCUCAACGAGGCGGCCGCCAACAGGGUGUCGGUGUCGCAGCGGCGGAACACCACCACGGGUGCUUCGGCCGCUUCCGCCGCCUCGGCCAUGGCCUCCCUCACGGCCUCGCGGGCCCACAGCCUCGGAGGCCUGGACCCGGCCUUCACCAGCACAGAGGACCUAAACUGCAAGGAGAACUUGGAGCAGGACCUCGGCGAUGACAACAGCAACGACCUGCUGCUCAGCUGCCCGCACUUCCGCAAUGAGAUCGGGGGCGAGUGUGAGCGCAACGUGAGCUUCUCCCGGGCUUCCGUGGGCUCCCCGAGCAGCGGCGAGGGCCACCUGGCAGAGCCCGCCCUGAGCGCCUACCGCACCAACGCCAGCAUCUCGGUGUUGGAAGUUCCCAAGGAGCAGCAGCGGACGCAGAGUCGGCCCCGGCAGUACAGCAUCGAGCAUGUGGACCUGGGCGCCCGCUACUACCAGGAUUACUUCGUGGGCAAAGAACAUGCCAAUUACUUCGGCGUGGAUGAGAAGCUGGGGCCAGUGGCUGUGAGCAUUAAGCGGGAGAAGCUGGAAGACCACAAGGAGCACGGACCUCAGUACCAGUACAGGAUCAUCUUCCGGACCCGCGAGCUCAUCACCCUGCGGGGCUCCAUCCUGGAAGAUGCUACGCCCACAGCCACCAAGCAUGGGACCGGGCGGGGCCUGCCCUUGAAGGAUGCCCUGGAGUAUGUCAUCCCCGAGCUCAACAUCCACUGCCUGCGGCUGGCCCUCAACACCCCCAAGGUGACGGAGCAACUGCUGAAGCUCGAUGAGCAAGGGCUCUGCCGGAAGCACAAGGUGGGCAUCCUCUAUUGCAAGGCCGGCCAGAGCUCCGAGGAGGAGAUGUACAACAAUGAGGAGGCCGGCCCCGCCUUUGAGGAGUUCCUCUCCCUCAUCGGCGAGAAGGUCUGCCUGAAGGGCUUCACCAAGUACGCUGCCCAGCUGGACGUCAAGACCGACUCCACGGGAACCCACUCCCUCUACACGAUGUACCAGGACUACGAGAUCAUGUUCCAUGUCUCCACCCUGCUCCCUUACACCCCCAACAACAGGCAGCAGCUGCUACGGAAGAGGCACAUAGGAAAUGACAUCGUGACGAUCAUCUUCCAGGAGCCUGGCGCGCUACCGUUCACCCCCAAGAACAUCCGCUCCCACUUCCAGCACGUCUUCAUCAUUGUCCGAGUCCACAACCCCUGCACUGAUAACGUCUGUUACAGUAUGGCUGUGACCCGAUCCAAAGACGCUCCUCCUUUCGGCCCCCCCAUCCCCAGUGGAACCACAUUCCGCAAAUCCGACGUCUUCAGAGACUUCUUGCUGGCCAAGGUGAUUAACGCUGAGAACGCCGCGCACAAGUCCGACAAGUUCCACACCAUGGCCACCAGGACCCGCCAGGAGUAUCUCAAGGACCUGGCCGAAAACUGUGUCUCCAACACCCCCAUCGACUCCACCGGCAAAUUCAACCUCAUCUCCCUGACCUCCAAGAAGAAGGAAAAGACAAAAGCACGGGCUGGCGCUGAGCAGCACAGUGCAGGGGCCAUCGCCUGGAGGGUGGUGGCCCAGGACUACGCCCAGGGGGUGGAAAUCGACUGCAUUUUGGGAAUUUCCAAUGAGUUUGUGGUGCUCCUGGACUUACGCACCAAGGAGGUGGUGUUCAACUGCUACUGCGGGGAUGUCAUUGGCUGGACUCCAGACUCCUCCACACUCAAAAUCUUCUAUGGACGAGGAGACCACAUCUUCCUACAGGCGACAGAGGGUUCUGUGGAGGACAUAAGGGAGAUAGUGCAGAGACUGAAGGUGAUGACCAGUGGCUGGGAGACGGUGGACAUGACGCUUCGGCGGAACGGGCUCGGGCAGCUGGGCUUCCACGUGAAGUACGACGGCACGGUGGCCGAGGUUGAGGACUAUGGGUUCGCCUGGCAGGCCGGCCUCCGGCAGGGCAGCCGACUAGUGGAGAUCUGCAAGGUGGCCGUGGUCACACUGACCCACGACCAGAUGAUCGACCUGCUGCGCACCUCUGUCACUGUGAAGGUGGUCAUCAUCCCGCCUUUUGAGGACGGCACUCCCCGGAGGGGUUGGCCGGAGACCUACGACAUGAAUACCUCGGAGCCCAAGACGGAGCAGGAAAGCAUCACUCCUGGGGGCCGGCCCCCCUACCGCAGCAAUGCUCCCUGGCAGUGGAGCGGGCCCGCAUCCCAUAACUCUCUACCAGCCUCCAAGUGGGCCACUCCAACCACUCCCGGCCAUGCCCAGUCCCUGAGCCGGCCCCUGAAGCAGACCCCCAUAGUCCCCUUCCGGGAGUCCCAGCCACUGCACAGCAAGAGGCCUGUCAGCUUCCCAGAAACCCCUUACACAGUAUCACCAGCAGGGGCCGACAGAGUCCCUCCCUACCGACAGCCUUCUGGGAGCUUCUCCACCCCCGGUUCGGCCACCUACGUGAGAUACAAGCCAUCCCCAGAAAGGUACACGGCUGCCCCACACCCCCUGCUAUCUCUUGAUCCCCACUUCAGCCACGAUGGGACGUCCAGCGGCGACUCCUCUUCCGGCGGCCUGACCAGCCAGGAGAGCACCAUGGAACGCCAGAAGCCAGAGCCUUUGUGGCAUGUGCCUGCCCAGGCCAGGCUCUCAGCCAUAGCCGGAAGCAGCGGGAACAAGCACCCGUCCAGGCAGGAUGCAGCAGGCAAAGAUUCCCCCAACAGGCAUUCCAAAGGAGAACCUCAAUACUCAAGUCAUUCCAGCAGCAACACCCUCUCCAGCAACGCAUCCAGCAGCCACAGCGACGACCGCUGGUUCGACCCCCUGGACCCCCUGGAGCCAGAGCAAGACCCCCUCUCCAAGGGUGGCUCUAGUGACAGCGGCAUCGACACCACCCUCUACACCUCCAGCCCUAGCUGCAUGUCCCUGGCCAAGGCUCCACGGCCCGCCAAGCCACACAAGCCCCCUGGAAGUAUGGGCCUUUGUGGCGGGGGUCGCGAGGCCGCUGGGAGGUCCCACCACGCAGACAGGCGGCGGGAGGUCUCCCCUGCCCCCGCAGUUGCCGGCCAAAGCAAGGGCUACCGACCGAAGCUGUACUCCUCCGGCUCCAGCACCCCCACGGGACUGGCGGGGGGCAGCCGAGACCCACCGAGGCAGCCCAGUGACAUGGGCUCGAGGGUUGGCUACCCCGCUCAGGUUUACAAAACUGCCAGUGCAGAGACUCCUCGGCCCUCCCAGCUGGCCCAGCCCAGCCCCUUUCAGCUCUCCGCCUCCGUCCCCAAGUCCUUCUUCUCCAAGCAGCCUGUACGCAAUAAGCACCCAACAGGGUGGAAGAGAACGGAGGAGCCCCCACCACGGCCACUCCCCUUCAGUGACCCAAAGAAGCAGGUGGACACGAACACCAAAAAUGUCUUUGGGCAACCGAGGUUGAGGGCAUCCCUCCGAGACCUCCGGUCACCACGGAAGAACUACAAAUCCACCAUCGAGGAUGACCUGAAGAAACUCAUCAUCAUGGACAACCUGGGGCCAGAGCAGGAGAGAGACACGGGACAGUCACCGCAGAAGGGCCUGCAGCGGACGCUGUCGGACGAGAGCCUGUGCAGCGGGCGCCGGGAGCCCAGCUUCGCCAGCCCCGCUGGCCUAGAGCCAGGGCUGCCCAGCGACGUGCUCUUCACCAGCACCUGCGCCUUCCCGUCCAGCACGCUGCCUGCACGCCGCCAGCACCAGCACCCCCACCCGCCCGUCGGCCCCGGUGCCACCCCUGCCGCCGGCAGCGGCUUUCCCGAGAAGAAAUCCACCAUCUCAGCCUCGGAGCUCUCGCUGGCUGAUGGGCGGGACCGCCCCCUGCGGCGCCUGGACCCUGGGCUGAUGCCCCUGCCUGACACAGCUGCUGGCCUCGAGUGGUCCAGCCUGGUGAACGCAGCCAAGGCAUACGAAGUGCAAAGAGCCGUCUCACUCUUCUCUCUGAACGACCCGGCCCUGAGCCCGGACAUCCCGCCUGCACACAGUCCUGUCCACAGCCACCUGAGCCUGGAGAGGGGACCCCCGACCCCCAGGACCACCCCUACCAUGAGCGAGGAGCCACCCCUGGAUCUGACAGGCAAGGUGUACCAGCUGGAGGUGAUGCUGAAACAGCUGCACACUGACCUGCAGAAGGAGAAGCAGGACAAGGUGGUGCUCCAGUCAGAGGUGGCCAGCCUGCGGCAGAACAACCAGCGGCUGCAGGAGGAGUCGCAGGCCGCCAGCGAGCAGCUGCGCAAGUUUGCGGAGAUCUUCUGCAGGGAGAAGAAGGAGCUCUGAGGUGGGAGGCCGCCGCCCGCCUUCGCUCCUUCCCCUCAGGCCGUGGCCCUGCUGCCUCUCUCCCUCCACUCAGCUCCCAGCUGCCGGUGUGACCAAGAUGACCCAUCCAGGGCCCUCCCCAUGGACACGGAAACUCCGAUGGCCUCACUAGGGCUGUGAGUCAGGGUCAGCGCGCACAGCCCUCAUGCCCCAGAGGGCGAAGUGGUCUCAGGCCUCCCUCCAAGCUGCCCAGCUGUGGUCCCGGUGAGCUGGGCUGUGCUUACACCGCUCCCGGGCCUGCCCCGCUGUCCCCAUCUAGCCUCUUCCUGGGACCAGCCCUUCGAAGCUGAUGGGGACGGAGAGAGGAGCCAGUCUCCAGACGCCUCGGCUCCAGGAGGUCACACAGCAGGUUUCUGCACCACGCACAACAAAGUUGCGGCUUGUGGGGCCGAGGCCCCUGCAUGAAAAGUACAGCGUGAAAGCAACCCUUUCUUCCCCACACCCAGAGAGGUGAGGCCCGCGUGGACACAGACCAGGGCGCCUCGGUCCCUAGCACGUGAGCUCCAAAAAGCACGAACAUGAUCCCCUCCCUAACCCCCUCCUCCCAAAAAGCAGCCAGGAGCACUUUCUUAGAGUUUAAAUUAUUUUCUUGGGGGCCUGAGGAUAGAGAGAGGCAAGGCUAGCCUCCAGAGCCGAUUUAUUUGAGAGAGAAACUCUAUUUGGAUCUCCAGGACGGUUUAUACGAUCUUUUUCUAUCAGCUCCUCUUCCGCCAGAGGCCACUGCACCUGGGCUAGGGGUCCACAGGCCCCUCCACCUUCCAGCUAACCAGGCCAGGCCGGGGCGGUGGAGCCACCACACAGCCGACUCUCUCCUCCUCCUCCCGGCACGACCUGGCCCUGACCAGCAGCCUCGGCCUCUUCUGGGUUCCAGGAGGGGCUCCCGAAGCCCUCAGGACAGGGCUGGAGGAGAACAGCCUUCAUCUCCUCCUCUGGUUUUUUUUUCCUUUGCAAGUCUCCCAGCCCAUCUCUCCGAGCAGCGGCCACCAGACCCCCUCACCAUGCUCCCCGGGGAGCACUGCACCCCGCGAACCCCACUGGACGCUGGUUCUCUAAAGGCAAUAAGGGGCGGCCAUGCCGGUGUGGUACCACGCUGUUCCUCCAGGAAACCGUUUCUUUUUUUCCUUCUUUAAAAGCAAACAGAAAAAGAUAUAUAUAUAUAUAUAUAUAUAUUUAUUUUUUCAUGUAGAGUUGGCGCCAGAACAAGCCUGUAUGGCCACAGUCUGUGGAUUCAUCCCCCCAACCUCAAGCUGAGGACCAAGGCGUGUCCCCUGUGGGCUGGGGGUCAGUGGGAGGACCAGAGGGAUGAAGUCAGGGCAGGCCGGUGCCCUUUUUGGGAGGCACCAGGCGGGGAGGAGUUGGCGGAGCAGGUCUGGCUGUGAGCCAGCACCAGGCAACCCGGCCCUUGUCCAGGGACCUCUGCUGCCUUCUCUCUGGGGUCAGGAACCUCAGAGGAGGGGGCUCUGGGGACUGCAUAGGACGCAGGCACUCGGAGGUGCCGGUGUGGAUGGGUGGGGGUGAGAGAAGAGGGUUCUUAUCGCGUCUCCUGUGAUCAGCCUCUGGCCCCCUGGAGGAGGAAACCUCAGCGCUGCCCCUGCCCCCACCCUCACCCCCAACACCAAGAGUGAGGUGGGCGUGCCCCAGGCAGCGUCCUCAGCCCUGGCCAGCUACUGUGAUGCCAUCUUCUCCCCCAUCCCCUUCUCUGGGGGGCCCACCCGUCCCCCACCCCCACCCCUUAGACCCUCAUCGGGUCCCUUUUUUUUUUUUUUUUUCAGUUGUCUCCUCCCAUCUUCAGAUCAUUCGAAUCAUUUUGGGGACUUAAUCAUGUACAUGGACAAGUGUAAAUUAUGAUUUUUGGUUUUGUUUUCUGUUAUUUUUUAAGGAUUUCUGCAAAAACAGAUCUAUUUAAUUUGAGGUUGAUGUUCUAUCCAAUGGCCGAAGAUAGCAGCAGGUUUUUUUUUUCAUAUGUUGAUUUGUUUCAUUUGGAUUUUUUUUUUAUUAUUCUUUAUUGUCUUUUUUUUUUCCCCAUCCCUGUCUUGAGAUUUUCUGGCAUGUUUCUGGAGGUUUCAAAGGAAAUAAAGGUUUCAUAGAAA